ACUAGUAGCUGGUGCUCCAGGCUGGCGGCGCUCACCUUUCUCCUAGCCGGGUGACCCAGGGGAUUUAUUUUAUGUUGGCUUUCUCUGAAAUGCCAAAGCCACCCGAUUAUUCAGAGCUGAGUGACUCUUUAACGCUUGCCGUGGGAACAGGAAGAUUUUCGGGACCAUUGCACAGAGCAUGGAGAAUGAUGAACUUCCGUCAGCGGAUGGGAUGGAUUGGAGUGGGAUUGUAUCUGUUAGCCAGUGCAGCAGCAUUUUACUAUGUUUUUGAAAUCAGUGAGACUUACAACAGGCUGGCCUUGGAACACAUUCAACAGCACCCUGAGGAGCCCCUUGAAGGAACCACAUGGACACACUCCUUGAAAGCUCAAUUACUCUCCUUGCCUUUUUGGGUGUGGACAGUUAUUUUUCUGGUACCUUACUUACAGAUGUUUUUGUUCCUAUACUCUUGUACAAGAGCUGAUCCCAAAACAGUGGGCUACUGUAUCAUCCCUAUAUGCUUGGCAGUUAUUUGCAAUCGCCACCAGGCAUUUGUCAAGGCUUCUAAUCAGAUCAGCAGACUACAACUGAUUGACACGUAAAAUCAGUCACCGUUUUUUCCCUACGAUUACAAAACUGCCAGUCCUAUAUGGAGUCUGAUCACAAGACUGCAGUUUCUUCACAGAUCUCAGGAAGUUGUCGUGGGGCAGAGGCUUUUUAAAAACAUGUGAUUAGGGAGCUAUCUUUAUCUGAAUAAUAACGAAUUUUUAGGUAAAACCUGAGAUAGAGUACUACAAAAUCAUGUUGAUGACUUCAGAUUUUGGAAGUUAAAUCAUGUCUGUUAUUUGCAUUCUUUAGAAACUUGACUAAGUACCUGAAUUCAUAUUUCUAUUCUACUGUGCAACAUAGUGAUGAUUCAGAAAUUUUUCCUUUGGGGAAAAAAAUGAAUAUGAACAUUUCCAUUGUGUUAAGUGUAAAAAGGUCCAGACAUGAUCAUAAAAUUUAAAUUUUAUACAAUUACUUGGCUUGCUUUAAAAUUCUUCACACUUAAAACACCGAUUCAUUCUAUUGCAGCUAAGCCAGCUGUCUAGACUUGCUGUCAGCUUAUGAGGCAUUGCUAAAAAAUUAUUGAGGAAAUGGCUGUCUUGAUAAGCAGAAUUUGUUCUUCCUCUUGGUAAUGGCUAAAUUAUUAUUAAUGCUUUUAAUGGUUUUAUUUUUUAUAUUUUUCUUUUUUGUGGAGAAUGGGGUCUCGCUAUGUUGCCCAGGCAGGUCUCGAACUCCUGGGCUCAAGCUUUCCUCCUCUCUCUGGCUCCCUAAGUGCUAGGAUUACAGGUGUGAGCUACCAUGCCCAGCUAUUUUUAAUUAAAAAAAUUUUUUUUUUCCAUGACUUGUGACACAGUCUCAGAAGGCCCUGAGAACGUACGCUCCAAUGCUACUGAUUUAGAAAACUAUCUGGGAAGAAACUAAGUGUUAAAUGUUGAAAGGCUAGAAAUAACUUACAAAUAGAAGAUGGAAACAAUGUGUUCAAUGAAAAUCUAGCAGGUUAUUUAUUAUUUAUUUAAAUUAUUAUUAUUAUUUUUGAGACGGAGCCUUGCUUUGUCACCCAGGAUGGAGUGCAGUGGUGCAGUCUUGGCUCACUGGAACCUUCGGCUCACUGCAACCUCCACCUCUCGGGUUUAAGCGAUUCUCUUGCCUCAGCCUCCUGAGUAGCUGGGAUUACAGGUGACCACCACCAUGCCUGGCUGAUUUUUGUUAUUUUAGUAGAGACAGGGUUGCAGCAUGUUGGCCAGGCUGGUCUCAAACUCCUCACCUAACUAAGGUAAUCCACUUGCGUCAGCCUCCCAAAGGCCUGGGAUUACAGGCAUGAGCCACCAUGCCUAGCUGUAUUUAUUUAUGUUAUUUAUUUUGAGAUGGAGUCUUGCUCUGUAGCCCAGACUGGUGUGCAGAAGUGCGAUCUCAGCUCACUGCAACCUCCACCUCCCAGGUUCAUGCUAUUCUCCUGCCUCAGACUCCCGAGUAGCUGGGAUUACAGGCACCCACCACCAUGCCUGGCUAAUUUUUGUAUUUUUAGUAGAGACGGGGUUUCACCAUGUUGUCCAGGCUGGUCCCGAACUCCUGACCUCAAGUGAUACACCUCAGCCUCCCAAAGUACUAGGAUAACAGGCAUGAGCCACCAUGGCCAGCCUAUAGCAGGUAAUUUAGUCCAGUCCUUAUCAGAUGCAUGAGACCCCUCUAAAAGAUGCUAUCAAGUCAUAAUCUUUCUGAUUUUCUUUUCUGGCCCAAGGUCAGGUCAUCAGGCAGUAGGUUAAUUACAUGAAGAUGUGUUCCUGUACCUUCUCCUUUGCAUUUGUACUACCUCACAUCUGGUACUAAUACAAAUAACUAAAACAUGGA